GGAGGCAGCUAACUCUAGGCUGUUACUCCUGAUCGCGUUGCCAUUGCCGACACGGGUACACUCUUCAUUCCUUAACAUGUGCUGUUCUGUUCUAGGACCGUGACAAACACUCAUCGUUGGGUGGGGCUCUAGUGCAGUCCGUUGGUGCCAAUAUUUUAUAAGCGACGUUUUCAAACUAUGUGAAGAUCCUUUCUUUUCUUUUCUUUCUUUCUUUUUUUUUUUUUUUUUUUUUUUUUUUUGAGACGGAAUCUCGCUCUGUCGCCCGGGCUGGAGUGCAGUGGCGCGAUCUCGGCUCACUGCAACCUGCGCCUCCCAGGUUCACGCGAUUCUCCUGCCUCAGUCUCCUGAGUUGCUGGGACUACGGGCGCCCAUCACCACACCCGGCUAAUUUUUUGUAUCUUUAGUAGAGACGGAGUUUCAGUAUGUUGGCCAGACUGGUCUCGAACUCCUGACCUCAGGUGAUCUGCCCGCCUCAGCCUCCCAAAGUGCUGGGAUUACAGGCGUGAGCCACCAUUCUCGGCUGAAGAUCCAUUUUAAGAAGAUUUAUUCCUCUAUGAUGGAGAAGUAUGAAAAAAUUGGGAAAAUUGGAGAAGGAUCCUAUGGAGUUGUUUUCAAAUGUAGAAACAGGGACACGGGUCAGAUUGUGGCCAUCAAGAAGUUUCUGGAAUCAGAAGAUGACCCUGUCAUAAAGAAAAUUGCCCUUCGGGAAAUCCGAAUGCUCAAGCAACUCAAGCAUCCCAACCUUGUUAACCUCCUGGAAGUCUUCAGGAGGAAACGGAGGCUUCACCUGGUGUUUGAAUAUUGUGACCACACAGUUCUCCAUGAGUUGGACAGAUACCAAAGAGGGGUACCAGAACAUCUCGUGAAGAGCAUAACUUGGCAGACACUGCAAGCUGUAAAUUUUUGCCAUAAACACAAUUGCAUACAUAGAGACGUGAAGCCAGAAAAUAUCCUCAUCACGAAACAUUCCGUGAUUAAGCUUUGUGACUUUGGAUUUGCUCGGCUUUUGACUGGACCGAGUGACUACUAUACAGACUACGUGGCUACCAGGUGGUACCGCUCCCCUGAGCUGCUGGUGGGGGACACGCAGUACGGCCCCCCGGUGGAUGUUUGGGCAAUUGGCUGUGUCUUUGCUGAGCUGCUGUCAGGAGUGCCUCUGUGGCCAGGAAAAUCGGAUGUGGAUCAGCUGUAUCUGAUUAGGAAGACCUUGGGGGAUCUCAUUCCUAGGCACCAGCAAGUGUUUAGCACGAAUCAGUACUUCAGUGGAGUGAAAAUUCCAGACCCUGAAGAUAUGGAACCACUUGAAUUAAAAUUCCCAAACAUCUCUUAUCCUGCCCUGGGGCUCCUAAAGUUUCAUCUUUCAAAGAAGAAAAAAAUGACAUUAAUAAGUUAAUACAAUUUUGAAGAAGUAAGAAGAAGGAAUUUUCUGUUCUUUUAGGGCUGUCUCCACAUGGACCCUACUCAAAGGCUGACAUGUGAACAGCUGUUGCAUCACCCAUAUUUUGAAAACAUCAGAGAAAUAGAGGAUUUGGCAAAAGAACACAACAAACCAACAAGGAAGACCCUAAGAAAGAGCCGAAAGCACCACUGCUUUACAGAAACAUCCAAGGUUAUAAUUUGAAAUGAUCUCCUACCUGCCACCUGGUACAGAGAGUUGGAAUCUAGACUUGAGGAUGGCAGUUGUGGCUUUCAGCUCCAGCAUCCUCAUUCCAGCACUAGGAGACAGGUCAUAGGAUCUAUCAACCAGGGCCCCAGGGACAUCUGUCUCCUGAAGCCCCCUCUCCCUGAAUCCUAAAGGUGCCCUUGUCCUGCUGCUUCCUGAUGCCACACAGGGGCCAGGGUUUCCAGCCUGCAUGAGCACAGGUCUCAACAAGGUACAUGAGUAUGAGUCCAGCUAAGGAGACUUUUUGGGCUUUGGAAAAUGAAAUCAGAUUUUCCCCAUGCAGUUCUGUGUCAUCAUGUACACUUUUAGUAUUAAAACUAACACUCCAGGUUUGUCCAAAAAAGGAGCUGUUUUCCUCCCUGAUCCUUUGUCAGAGUUGGCUAGGGCAAAUACAGUGAUGAGUGCUUUUGGUGGUAUCAGCUGAAUACAUUUAACCAGAGAACAGCAUCCAAACUGCACACUGGGAGACUGUGAAGAAUCCUGAUUGGUAUAAAAUGGCCUUACAUUAAGCAUCUUGUGAUAAGCCAAAAGCUGUAAUAAUUUAGAAUGAACUGUAGUUGGAACCACAACUGAUCCUGGGUAACCUCAGGAUCUACCUAGGUACUCCUUAAGCUAUACAUUAUCUUGCCUUAGUCUUUCUCUUUGCAGCUUCCACUGCCCAGCAUGCUGAAUGGUACCAGGGUGUGUUGUGUAUGAGGCUGGGAGGAGGGAAAAGGGUGAAAAAGGUCCAUGAGGAACAAGUACAGCAUGAACUCCAGGGCCCUAAUGUAGAUCACAGUUACAAAAUUAAUGUUUUAUUCUCCAUCAUAUGUGACCCAGGUAGCACAACAGGCCAGAAACAGACUCCUCCACCCCCACGCCAGAAUUAUUCCUUAUCUCAGUAUUAGUUUGUAUUCGAGAGCAAAAGGUUUUGAUGGAAAUAUUUCUAUUUGAAAAAAUAGGGAAACUCCACUAUUUGGUGUAUUGAUUUUUUUUGAGACUGAGUCUCACUCUGUCGCUCAGGCUAGAGUGCAGUGGUAUGAUCUUGGCUCACUGCAACCUCUGCCUCCCAGGUUCAAGUGAGUCUCCUGCCUCAGCCUCCCCAGUAGCUGGGAUUACAGGCAUGUGCCAGUAUGCCUAACUAAUUUCUAUAUUUUUAGUAGAGACAGGGUUUCGCCAUGUUGGCAGGCUGGUCUCGACUCCUGACCUCAGGUGAUCCAUCCGCCUUGGCCUCCCAAAGUGCUGGGAUUACAGGCAUGAGCCACCGCACCUGGCCUGGUGUACUGCUUUUAAAUCCUGAAAGAAUCAACUGAUUUAAAAGUACUAAAAAGCACUUUUCUGAGGACAAUGGCUGAAAAAUUUUUUUCUAGAAAGUAAAAGUACUAAACAGUUCCCUUUUUAGGGAUACCGAAGGACAUAUAGUGCAAUACAAAAAAUACAGGUGUGUUCUUUCAUUUGACAUUGACAAUAAAUUCAAACAUUUUCAGGAAGCUUGAAGGAAGCAGUUUGUCUUUUUUCUUUAGAGAUGGGGAUCUUGCUAUGUUGCCCAGGCUGCUCUCCUGGGCUCAAGGGAUGCUCCCACUCAGCCUCCCUUGUAGCUGGAACUACAAGUGUACACUGUGCCAUGCUUGAUUUGCCUUUUUAACUAAGGGAAGAGAGUGAGUAGGCAAAUUGCCUAGGUGCUCUGUUUAUCAGUUUUCUCCGCUAUAAGACAAGGCAUUGGCUUAAAUGAUCCCUAAGAUCUCAGCAAGCUCUCAACUCCUGUAAAUCUAUGUUUUCUUCCCAAUAAUGUUAACAUGUAGAUUUUCCCCUUUUCAUAUUCUCUAAAUCUUCUUUAAUGUGAAUGUUUUUCCUUUUUAAUAUAAACAUUUAAAAGGAAAAGCCAAGACGAAAUUGAAACAUUUAAUCCUCUCUCAAGUCCUGGAUUGUGUGCAAAAAAAGUACUUCUAUACUAAAAAGCUUAAUUACCUCUUUUGUGAUAUAUUCUAAAUAAUGAAAAAAAUGCAUGGCACAGUUUUGAACCUAAUUCUGUGUUUUGCAUUUUUAGUUGCAGUACCUACCCCAGCUAACUGGCAGCAGCAUCCUUCCAGCUUUGGAUAAUAAGAAGUACUACUGUGAUACCAAGAAACUUAACUACCGUUUUCCAAACAUUUAAAGGAGCUAGGAGACAUGAUUUUAAAAAAGGAAUCAAUAGAUGCUUUGAAGAAAAUAAAACUUAUACAGUUGAUUGAAAACAAUUACAAUGUUGAAAACACACCAGGAGAAAACAUAAGCAAGAAACUGGGAGGCCAACUGGCAAGAUAUGAAGGGAAAUUCCAGAUCCAGUCUUCCAUGCUUGAUGAUGGUGUCCAGAAAAGAAAAAACCUGUUUGGAGUUGCACUUGUAUUUCAGUUUAUGUAAGUAGCCGAACUUAUGGACAGAAUAUGAACUGUCCCAUACCUCUGGCAAAACUAGAUGAUAUCAAAAAGAUUUAUGCUUCAGUUGUACCACAUGCCACACAAGAAAAAUGAACCACAAAAUGCCCAUAUAUAUUUCCUCGGAUCUCUGUUGCCUGAGUCCUAUCUCCUGCCUCUCAGAUUGUUUCAGCAUCAUAUUUAAGAUAGUUCUAUUUCUUGAAAUCAAAAUGUUUAAAAUCCCAUUUCCUGCUUGCUCUAUUUCUUGAUUUUUAUAUUUUAAAACAUUUUGAGGGUAACACUUAGGUUCAAAAUAUUUAAAAGCAUAUGAAUUAUCACAAAAGCUUGGUAAUUUAUAAUUUAAUUAUAUGUUUCCACAUUUCAUCCUUACUUUAUCAGUAAAGGAUACACCUUAGUCACUUUUGCAGGCAACGUGGAUUUACUGUAAUCUGUCUACAUUUAUUCACCCAAUUCCCCUUGUAAACAAUGGCAUGAAGCUCGGCAGCUGAUUAAGGCAGUCAAAGGGUAGAGCAAGACCUACAGGCUUUGCAGGAACUGAACCUAUCAGCCUGAAAAUAAUUAGUAUUUCAUUCUCUCUGGCACAGCCUUUGACCUGGUACAUCUAUAGGCAAACCUGUAAUUCAGUGAUCUGGGUUUCAGAAGAAAUUACUUGUGAGCUUUUACUUGAGUCAUGAAAGACAUUAUGUUGUAAACUGAUGUUUUCCCUGAAACAUCUUUUUGCACUAUGUUUGUAUGUGUAUGUAUGUGUAUGUAUAUAUAUAUAUAUAUAUAUAUAUAUGCUAUUCUAACAACUAAUAUAUUACACUAAGUAGUCCAAAGUAUUGAGGACUCAUAGCUUUGCACAGUGAGACUUAAAAUGAUGACACACACACACAUAUAUAUAUAUGUGUUUUUUAUAUAUAUAUAUAAAACCUGCCACCUCAGCCUCCCAAGUAGCUGGGACUGCAGGCAUGUGCCACUAUACUGGCUAAUUUUUUUGUAUUUUUUGGUAGAGGCAGGGUUUUGCCAUGUUCCCCAGGCUGGUCUUGAACUCCUGGGCUCACGUGAUCUGAGCGCCUUGGCCUUCCAAAGUGCUGGCAUUACAGGCAUGAGCCACUGCGCCUGGCCAAAAUGACAUAAUUAGCUUUGAUUUGGUCUACUGCUCUUAAUCAAAAAGCUUUUUCAUCCUUGUCCCCUGGACACAAGGGCAAUAUGAAGCCUGACGUCUGUUUCUUACAGCUCAACACCAUUUCUGGUUGAUGUGCUGCCACUAUUCCUAGCACUUCUCAGCCAUGGUCUUCAAAGUUGUAUUUCACUCUAUUUUCAAAACAUUUCUUCUGUACUCUCAUUUUCUUCCUGUUAAUUUUCUUCAUGAUGACAUCUGACCCCAUUUACUUAAGUAAUCCACUGAGGUCUGGUGUCUACUCAAUAAUUUUGACUACCCUAGGCAGUUUAAUGAUAUCCUAAGGCUUCCUAAUGUAUGUCUUUUCUUGCCUAGACCUGAUAUGGGUUAAAUGCUAGUCCCUGAAUUAUUCAAUUCCUGUUAGACGGCCUUGAUUCAAAUGACAAGGAAGAACAUCCAGCUUCCGUGAAUAGUUAAAAAAAAAUUUUUUUUUCCUUAACCCAAGAAAAUACACUUGACGGAGGCAGAUUACUAUAACAGCCUAAUAAUUCAGCCAAUAGUUUUACCAAAAACUAUUCAGAAUAGAAAAGUAGCUCUAGACUAAAUCGUGGUGAAUCAGUUGUCUCACCAUACAGUAAUGAAACAAACCUGAGAAAAAAGGCUUAUUUUUUUCUAAUGAGUUCCGUUAAAUUUAUGCUUAUGUUCAAUUUAACCAUAUUUAUAAUGCUUUUAUUCGGUAUGAAAUCUCCACUGUAUCACAUGAGACUCUUCCACAUCCUUUUAUUUACUAUUUUCUGAUUUUUAAAAUGACAGUGGCAAUUACCAUUUAUACUGUGUUAUUUGUAUAAGCUGUUAAACACAACAUUGUUAAACACAACGAAAAUUCAUUUUUCUACCUGAAAGCUGUAUCAUAGAAAAUUAUUUUCAAGUUUAUAUUCAACAGCUUAAUAAUGUUCAAACCAGGCUGGGCGCGGUGGCUCCCAGCACUUUGGGAGGCCGAGGCGGGUGGAUCCUGAGGUUAGGAGUUCAAGACCAGUCUGGCCAAGAUGGUGAAACCCUGUCUCUACUAAAAGUACAAAAAUUAGCUGGGCGUGGUGGUGGGCGCCUGUAAUCCCAGCUACCUGGGACGCUGCGACAGAGAACUGCUUGAACCCGGGAGGCAGAGGUUGCAGUGAACUGAGAUCACACCACUGCACUCCAACCUGGGCAACAGAGUGAGAGUCUGUCUCAAAAAAAAAAAAAAAAAAAAAAAAGUUCAAAUCAAACACACAGAAAUCUAUAAACAAACUGGCAUAUAAGAGUAAUAGAAUCAGGGCCAUUUCUCACAGGUAACAAUGAAGACCUGUUUUAUCUAUUUUUCACUUUUUUUUUUUUUUUUGAGACAGGGUCUUAAUCUGUUGCCCAGGCUGGAGUGCAGUGGUGCCAACAUGGCUCACUGCAGCCUCGACUUCCCGGGCUCAACUGAUCCUCCUACCUCAGACUCCUGAGUAGUUGGGACUACAGGCAUGUGCCACUACACCCAGCUAUUUUUUAUUUUUUAAUUUUUUGGUAGAGACAGGGUUUUGCCAUGUUGCCCAGGCUCGUCCUGAACUCCUGGGCUCAAAUGAUCUGCCUGCCUUGGCCUUCAAAAGUGCUGGGAUUACAGGCCAGCCCUUUUUUUUAAGAGACAGGGUCUCCCCCUUUCACCCAGGCUACCAGGCUGGUGUGCAGUGGCCGUGAUCAUAGCUUACUGCAGCCUCAAACUCCUGAGCUCAAGCAAUCCUACCACCUCAACCUCCCAAGUAUCUGAGAUUACAGGUAUGCACCACCAUGCCUGCCUAAUUUUUAAAAUUUUUUUAGAGAUGGGGUCUCACUGUGUUGCCCAAAUUGGUCUCAAACUCCUGGUCUCAAGUGAUCCUCCCACCUCAGCCUCCCAAAGCACUGGGAUUACAGGCACGAGCCACGGCACCCAGCCUAAAGCAAUGUUAGGUUUCAAGAAAAACCUAAGCAUAGCCCACUAGUUUUUACUGUUUCCUUUAUUAUAUUGCAAUCUGCAAAACUAUUUGUAUUCAGCCAAGUAUCUAUGUCCAGUUUUAAUAAAAUAGUAGCCUAAGCUUACAAAAUAGACAAAUUAAGCAGCAACUGUUGAUUCUGAGUAAGUCUGUAUGCUAUCAAGAACACAAGAAUGCAGGAUCAUGGGAAAUGCACGCAAAUCCUGUUGAAGCAAUGCAUGCUUCAACAACCACUGACCACUUUGCAUAAUUGACUCCAUCAAUGAAUCUGUAAUUUAGCUUCUAAUUUUUCAUAAUUGUGCAUUUAUGGUAGUAUGCUUCACUAACUUUAAAGUUAAAUGUAAAUUACUGUUAUAAUAAAAACAUCUGUUGUACAAAUAA